AAAGAAGGACCUGGGCUUUGGGAAGAUCUAAAGACCCAGGAAGGUCUCUGGGUGGGUGAGUGCUUUCUCUGCUGUGGUGGAGCUGGUGACAGUUUAUUCUCCCAGGAGGUCCCUGGCUGUGGCUGACAGUUUCUGGAGGGCUGGCAGGCGUCUACCUGUGGCUUUCAGGAUAAAGCCAAGAUGAAACUCCCCUUACUUCUGGCUCUUCUAUUUGGGGCAGUUUCUGCUCUUCAUCUAAGGUCUGAGACUUCCACCUUUGAGACCCCUUUGGGUGCUAAGACGCUGCCUGAGGAUGAGGAGACACCAGAGCAGGAGAUGGAGGAGACCCCUUGCAGGGAGCUGGAGGAAGAGGAGGAGUGGGGCUCUGGAAGUGAAGAUGCCUCCAAGAAAGAUGGGGCUGUUGAGUCUAUCUCAGUGCCAGAUAUGGUGGACAAAAACCUUACGUGUCCUGAGGAAGAGGACACAGUAAAAGUGGUGGGCAUCCCUGGGUGCCAGACCUGCCGCUACCUCCUGGUGAGAAGUCUUCAGACGUUUAGUCAAGCUUGGUUUACUUGCCGGAGGUGCUACAGGGGCAACCUGGUUUCCAUCCACAACUUCAAUAUUAAUUAUCGAAUCCAGUGUUCUGUCAGCGCGCUCAACCAGGGUCAAGUCUGGAUUGGAGGCAGGAUCACAGGCUCGGGUCGCUGCAGACGCUUUCAGUGGGUUGACGGCAGCCGCUGGAACUUUGCAUACUGGGCUGCUCACCAGCCCUGGUCCCGCGGUGGUCACUGCGUGGCCCUGUGUACCCGAGGAGGCCACUGGCGUCGAGCCCACUGCCUCAGAAGACUUCCUUUCAUCUGUUCCUACUGAGCUGGUCCCAGCCAGCAGUUCAGAGCUGCCCUCUCCUGGGCAGCUGCCUCCCCUCCUCUGCUUGCCAUCCCUCCCUCCACCUCCCUGCAAUAAAAUGGGUUUUACUGAAAUGGAUUUAUUUUCUCCUCUGAUCGCGGAUCCACUCUGCUUAGCCCUCAUUGAAACUUCUUCCUUAUCAUCUCUCCCCACACCACAACUUUCAUAGAAGUGUCAGAAGCUACUACUCCUUGAGGAGGAGGAUGGAGGGUGGAGUUGGGUCUAUGGAGCCUUUUGGAGAUGGAGGAAUGGGCUCAGCUAGUUCUCUUCAUAGAACACCUGAUUACUGGGCACCUGCAUAGUGCUGCCAGGACCUUUCAAGGUUGUAGGUAGACUCCCAAUGGCCCAGUUUGCAUCUCUGUAACCAAAGGCCUUUUCUCUCUCUCUCUCCAACCCCAGAACUGUGGUUGGUUUUAUAUGUAAGGAAGUUAACAUGUCCCUGGGAACAGUCCACAACAUUCAGGAAUGAAUGUAUAAGUACCGCAAUCCCCGGCCCCUCAAGUGGAAUAAAUCUAACAUGUAUUGGGCACCAUUUCCCAGUGGCCUGCUGUGGUAGUUGGCCUUAUUCCAUGCAUUUUUAUGGGCUGCCUUCCCUUCCUCAACUGCAUUCUCUGCUCCUUCCUACUCUCUGCAACUCCCAAAUAAACACUUGUACGCAA